GAGGUGGAUCCUGCGCCUGGCCAGCCCCGCCUGGCCUUCCCUCCGGCCCACCUGGCCGCCAUGCGCCUCUCCUCCUCCCCACCUCGUGGCCCGCAGCAGCUCUCCAGCUUUGGCUCCGUGGACUGGCUCUCCCAGAGCAGCUGCUCAGGGCCGACCCACACCCCCAGGCCUGCCGACUUCUCCCUGGGGAGCCUCCCUGGCCCAGGCCAGACAUCCGGCGCCCGGGAGCCCCCUCAGGCCGUCAGCAUCAAGGAGGCCGCCGGGUCCUCAAAUCUGCCUGCGCCGGAGAGGACCAUGGCCGGGUUGAGUAAGGAGCCAAAUACCUUGCGGGCCCCCCGUGUCCGCACAGCCUUCACCAUGGAGCAGGUCCGCACCUUGGAGGGCGUCUUCCAGCACCACCAGUACCUGAGCCCUCUGGAGCGGAAGAGGCUGGCCAGGGAGAUGCAGCUCUCAGAGGUCCAGAUAAAAACCUGGUUUCAGAAUCGCCGCAUGAAACACAAACGGCAAAUGCAGGACCCCCAGCUGCACAGCCCCUUCUCGGGGUCUCUCCAUGCGCCCCCAGCUUUCUACUCAACGUCUUCUGGCCUUGCCAAUGGCCUGCAGCUGCUGUGCCCUUGGGCACCCCUGUCCGGGCCCCAGGCUCUGAUGCUGCCCCCUGGCUCCUUCUGGGGUCUCUGCCAAGUGGCACAAGAGGCCCUGGCAUCUGCGGGAGCUUCCUGCUGCGGGCAGCCUCUGGCGUCCCACCCCCCUACCCCAGGCCGGCCUUCGCUGGGACCAGCCCUGUCCACGGGGCCCCGGGGCCUGUGUGCUAUGCCACAGACGGGGGAUGCAUUUUGAGGAGGCACCUCUGACUCCCACACUCGCGGUCUUGCUGAUCGCACCUGGCUCCUACCUGGAGGACUCAGUUGUUCUGUUUACAUCCUGGUGGCACCUCUCACCCUGACCCACACAAAGGUUCUGGAGAUUACUGGAGAAUAUAUAUAAAUAUAUAUAUGUACGUAUAUAUGUAAAUACACAUAUACGUAUAUAUAAAUAUAUAUAUACAUAUGUGUGUGUAUAUAUAUAUAUAUUUUUUUUUUUUUUUUUUUUUUUGAGACGGAGUGUUGCUCUGUCACCCAGGCUGGAGUGCAAUGACGCAAUCUCGGCUCACUGCAACCUCCGCCUCCUGGGUUCAAGCGAUUCUCCAGCCUCAGCCUCCCGAGUAGCUGGGAUUACAGACACCCGCCACCACGCCCGGCUAAUUUUUUCUAUUUUUAGUAGAAAUGGGGUUUCACCAUGUUAGCCAGGCUGGUCUCAAACUCCUGACCCUGUGAUCCGCCCGCCUCGGCCUCCCAAAGUGCUGGGAUUACAGGCAUGAGCCACUGCACCCGGCCCUGAGAAUAUAUUUAUUAAAGCCACCUCUUCACUGAAAGUUACCGAAAGAGUCGGUUUAGGAAGGAAACGAAGGGUCAGUGAACAGAGUCAAAUGCAGAAGUGGGCUUGUCAUGGGUAGGGCUUUCGGCGUACGAUAAAAGGAUCAUUUGUUUUUUAAAAGGGGUUGGAAAAACUGGUUUUCCAGUUGGAAACAGUAAAGGUUGUAAGCUUUGUGUGUACAAAAGAAAACAGGGAAUGCAGGUGUGUUUAUAGCGUUGUGGUUCAAGUCCCUCUUAACAAGAACUCCAAAGCUGGAAAGCAGGAGGGAACAAAGGUGAACAUGAAGGCGAGGAUGCUGGGGCCCUGCAGUGCGCUCUAGGCUGUGCGUGAGCCGGGACUGUACCCACAGCUUGCUGAGGGCUGCUCUUCUUGGGCCAGGGAAAGCAGGGCAGCCGGGACCUGCGGCUGUGCCUGGACUGAAGCUGUCCCGCAGGUCCCCACCCUCCAACACGUGCUCACCUGUCCCCCUGCUCGCAGCAGCCUCGGGACAAAACAAUGACUCAAGGACAGCACUUCUUGCAGAAGGUCUGGAAGUGCCCAGAAUGGGAGGCACGGAAGCCCCUCCCGGGGAGGACUCCCGCGUUGAUGGACCGUUCUUGGUGCAGACUCCUGACUGCGUGCAUGAAACCUGAGACAAGUGCAAUUCCUUCCAUGUCGCCCCAGAGUGCCCAGGAGGCAGGCAGUGCGGGGUGCCCAGGCAGACGGGUUCAGCCUGCAGAACUGGAGGCGACCUGUGAAACCCACCCGGGCACCCCAACAGGAACAGAAGCGUGGUCCUGCGGCUGCGUCCCCAGCGAGUUUCACUUUCCCCUUGCUCGUUUCUCCCUUGUUGUAAGUGUUUACAACUGGCAUGUGCUUUUAAACGUCAGGUAAGAGGGGAACAGCUGCUGUACAUCGUCCUGGCGAGUGACAAUGUGACAGAAGCCUGGGCGAGGCCCUCGGAGGGCAGCAGCUGGACAGGGACUACUGGGUUUGGCCUGGACAGCACUGAUUUGUGGAUGUGGAUGGGGGCACGUUGUCCGUGAUAAAAGUACAAGUGCCCCUCA